GCGCGCUCGCCGCGGGCUCGGGCCGCGGUCGCGGCUUUGCGGCAGGCUGCGCGUCAGGCGGGGAGCGGGGCGCGCGGGCCGGGGAGGGGGCCGGGCGCGCUGCGGGCUCCGCGGCCGGACCAUGCGGGGCAGGGGCCGGUUGCAGGGCCGGGGGCUGCAGCCGGCGCCGAUGGCGGCCGACUAGGACCUGCCCGGCCGGCUGCCCCGCGCCCCGCCUCGCCCCGCAGCCCGGCCGGCCGGGAGGGAUGCGCUGUGCCGCCCAGCUCCUCUCCGUCCUGCCCAUGCCCUGAAGCAGAAAGUUUGGGGGCCGGGGGUUGUCUCCCUUCUCCCUCCUGCAAUGACUGCCCAAGGACUCUUGCUGCCCAGCCUCGACUGUGACCUGUCUUCGCUCCCCAGGUCGAAAUGAACUAUUCCAAGCUAUAACCAAGGCUCCCCCUUCUCGCCCCUCCCUCACCCGCCUUUAAGAAUUUUUUUUUUAAUUCAAGAAAUUGUGGUCUGCCAUCUCCCCUCCUUGUUAAUAAUUUAGACCCCAGGCCUCAUAUGAAUAUAAGAGGGGGUGCGGUCUUCCCCAAGACGGCGCGCUGGAAGGACAGAUUCCCCUUGCCGACCCACAUACACCAUGAAGAGGUGCAGAUCGGACGAGCUGCAGCAACAACAGGGCGAGGAGGAUGGAGCUGGGCUGGAAGAUGCCGCUUCCCACCUGCCGGGCGCGGACCUCCGGCCUGGGGAGACCACGGGUGCUAACUCUGCUGGCGGGCCAACUUCAGACGCCGGCGCUGCCGCGGCGCCCAACCCAGGUCCCCGAAGCAAGCCUCCUGAUUUAAAGAAUGGCCACUGCAUCUCCAGGCACUACGUUCCCAUUCCAGAUGGGAAGAUUUGGGAAGGGCCAGUGCCUUUAUCAGGAAAGCAAAAGUGCUCCCAGAAGCUCUCACCUUGCUUUUCGUUGGCCCAAACUGUGUCAUGUGGCUACUCCUAGCUGCAAGGGGAGUCUGAUGAAGCAGGAAUUUUUAGCAAGAAAAUCCAGCAGCUGUCAGAGGGCUCCAUGUUUGGCCACGGUCUGAAGCACCUGUUCCACAGCCGCCGUCGGUCUCGGGAAAGGGAGCACCAGACGUCUCAGGAUUCCCAGCAGCAUCAGCAGCAGCAGGGUAUGUCCGACCAUGACUCCCCAGAUGAGAAGGAGCGCUCUCCGGAGAUGCAUCGCGUCUCCUACGCCAUGUCCCUGCACGACCUGCCCGCCCGGCCCACCGCCUUCAACCGCGUGCUGCAGCAGAUCCGCUCCCGGCCCUCCAUCAAGCGGGGCGCCAGCCUGCACAGCAGCAGUGGGGGCGGCAGCAGCGGGAGCAGCAGCCGGCGCACCAAGAGUAGCUCCCUGGAGCCCCAGCGUGGCAGCCCUCACCUGCUGCGCAAGGCCCCCCAGGACAGCAGCCUGGCCGCCAUCCUGCACCAGCACCAGUGCCGUCCCCGCUCUUCCUCCACCACCGACACUGCUCUGCUGCUGGCCGACGGCAGCAACGUGUACCUCCUGGCUGAGGAGGCCGAAGGCAUCGGGGACAAGGUCGAUAAGGGAGACCUGGUGGCCCUGAGCCUCCCCGCCGGCCAUGGUGACACCGACGGCCCCAUCAGCCUGGACGUGCCCGAUGGGGCACCGGACCCCCAGCGGACCAAGGCCGCCAUUGACCACCUGCACCAGAAGAUCCUGAAGAUCACCGAGCAGAUCAAGAUUGAGCAGGAGGCUCGCGACGACAAUGUGGCAGAGUAUCUGAAACUGGCCAACAACGCGGACAAGCAGCAGGUGUCACGCAUCAAGCAAGUGUUCGAGAAGAAGAACCAGAAGUCAGCCCAGACCAUCGCCCAGCUGCACAAGAAGCUGGAGCACUACCGCCGGCGCCUGAAGGAGAUUGAGCAGAACGGGCCCUCGCGGCAGCCCAAGGACGUGCUGCGGGACAUGCAGCAGGGGCUGAAGGACGUGGGCGCCAACGUGCGCGCAGGCAUCAGCGGCUUUGGGGGCGGCGUGGUGGAGGGCGUCAAGGGCAGCCUCUCUGGCCUCUCACAGGCCACCCACACCGCCGUGGUGUCCAAGCCCCGGGAGUUUGCCAGCCUCAUCCGCAACAAGUUUGGCAGUGCUGACAACAUCGCCCACCUGAAGGACCCCCUGGAAGAUGGGCCCCCUGAGGAGGCAGCCCGGGCACUGAGCGGCAGUGCCACACUCGUCUCCAGCCCCAAGUAUGGCAGCGAUGAUGAGUGCUCCAGCGCCAGCGCCAGCUCAGCCGGGGCAGGCAGCAACUCUGGGGCUGGGCCUGGUGGGGCGCUGGGGAGCCCUAAGUCCAAUGCACUGUAUGGUGCUCCUGGAAACCUGGAUGCUCUGCUGGAAGAGCUACGGGAGAUCAAGGAGGGACAGUCUCACCUGGAGGACUCCAUGGAAGACCUGAAGACUCAGCUGCAGAGGGACUACACCUACAUGACCCAGUGCCUGCAGGAGGAGCGCUACAGGUACGAGCGGCUGGAGGAGCAGCUCAACGACCUGACUGAGCUUCAUCAGAACGAGAUGACGAACCUGAAGCAGGAGCUGGCCAGCAUGGAGGAGAAGGUGGCCUACCAGUCCUAUGAGAGGGCACGGGACAUCCAGGAGGCCGUGGAGUCCUGCCUGACCCGGGUCACCAAGCUGGAGCUGCAGCAGCAACAGCAGCAGGUGGUACAGCUGGAGGGCGUGGAGAAUGCCAACGCGCGGGCGCUGCUGGGCAAGUUCAUCAACGUGAUCCUGGCGCUCAUGGCCGUGCUGCUGGUGUUCGUGUCCACCAUCGCCAACUUCAUCACGCCCCUCAUGAAGACACGCCUGCGCAUCACCAGCACCACCCUCCUGGUCCUCGUCCUGUUCCUCCUCUGGAAGCACUGGGACUCCCUCACCUACCUCCUGGAGCACGUGUUGCUGCCCAGCUGAGUGGCCAGCCACACCAACCCUGUGCUCUCUGGCCCCCAGCUGGCCACACUUCUCCAGGAGGGACCCUUGGACUUCUUUGUGUGUCCAGUUUGGCCUCCUGCCCAAACUGUCCAUUCCAGCAGCUCCUGCCCCCUUCUCUGUACUUGCUUCUGUCUGACACCUUCUCCCUGUUGGCCUGAAGGGAGCUUAGAAUGCAGCCCUACCUGGAGAUAGUGCGGGCACCUGUGGCCAAGUGGAGCAGAGGUGGACAUGGGGUUGGAUUGUUUUGAUUAUUUAUAGUUACACAAGGACUUCUCCCAGCUGACCCUCAGGAUGCCCCAAGUCAGGAAGACCAUUAAGAAUAGGAGGAGAGGGCUCUGCCUCAACUUUCCUAGGAAAGAGCCCACCUCGGAGAUAGCUACGGUUUUCUCUGGUGGAGAUGGUGAGGAUGAAGGCUGGAGAGUGAGGGAGGAGGCUCUGCUGGCCGCAGAGAACACAGGGAUGGGAGGGUCCCUAGCCUUCGGGCACCUCCAGGGCCAGAGAGCAGGCUCAGAGCAGCUAGUGUGGAGCUCAGCAUCCCCACCCCACCCCUCCUCCCUGUAGAGCUGAUUUGAGGCCUCCUUCUGGGGCUGGGCUCUGCAGGCCAGGUGGGUGUGGCCUGUGUUUUCCCUUCUGUUCUUUCUGCCUGUACUGGAUCUGUUAUUUUCAGGGAAACAGGCCCCAGGGCCCCCCUGAGCCUCACCCUAAGCCCUUAGGCCUCUGAGAGUGCUGUUGGGUUCUAUUUAUUUAUUUAUUUGUUCCUUUGUUCCCUACCCGUGCCCCCAGUGUCUUCCCUGCUGAGUACCAGGAGAGGUCCUGCCCCAUCCUCUCUCUGAAGCCAGGGCCCUUCCAUUCCAUUUAGCCUUUGGAUCAUCCUGGCUGGGAGAAGUGGGACCGAGCCACCCAGCCCCACUAUCCCCAAGCAGCCCUACAGCCGGGAUGGGAGGCACGUGGCCUCUCUUUUAUCCGUCUAUUUAUUUUGUAAGUGUAUUCGUGUGGAGGAGGUUGUUGCUUUAUUUUUUUAAGGCUCUGGAGUGUUGUGUAUGGUUUCUUUUCACAUCCCAGCCUCCCAUGGGCACUUCUAAGAAGAGAGGGGAUUUCUUGGAAAAGGAGAGAGGAAUCCCCUAGAGCAGGGAAAGCAGUGCCUGCCAGCUGUUGUGCACCUUCCUGAGAAAUAAAUAUCCUCUAAAUUUUCAAACCA